AUUUAACCUUUGGGAACAAGGCAACUAGCGUCUGGCAGCAGGAAUCCAACCAGUGCCCUGAGUUCUGAGGCAGAGAGGAGGACAGAAGAAACAAGAGGCUGGAGAUUGUCAAAUUCAGUAUCCCAGUUGGCUCUUGAUUCUUGGUGAAACCAUCCCUCAGCUCCUAGAGGGAGAUUGUUAGAUCAUGAAACUAAUUACCAUCCUUUUCCUCUGCUCCAGGCUGCUACUAAGUUUAACCCAGGAAUCACAGUCCGAGGAAAUUGACUGCAAUGACAAGGAUUUAUUUAAAGCUGUGGAUGCUGCUCUGAAGAAAUAUAACAGUCAAAACCAAAGUAACAACCAGUUUGUAUUGUACCGCAUAACUGAAGCCACUAAGACGGUUGGCUCUGACACGUUUUAUUCCUUCAAGUACGAAAUCAAGGAGGGGGAUUGUCCUGUUCAAAGUGGCAAAACCUGGCAGGACUGUGAGUACAAGGAUGCUGCAAAAGCAGCCACUGGAGAAUGCACGGCAACCGUGGGGAAGAGGAGCAGUACGAAAUUCUCCGUGGCUACCCAGACCUGCCAGAUUACUCCAGCCGAGGGCCCUGUGGUGACAGCCCAGUACGACUGCCUCGGCUGUGUGCAUCCUAUAUCAACGCAGAGCCCAGACCUGGAGCCCAUUCUGAGACACGGCAUUCAGUACUUUAACAACAACACUCAACAUUCCUCCCUCUUCAUGCUUAAUGAAGUAAAACGGGCCCAAAGACAGGUGGUGGCUGGAUUGAACUUUCGAAUUACCUACUCAAUUGUGCAAACGAAUUGUUCCAAAGAGAAUUUUCUGUUCUUAACUCCAGACUGCAAGUCCCUUUGGAAUGGUGAUACCGGUGAAUGUACAGAUAAUGCAUACAUCGAUAUUCAGCUACGAAUUGCUUCCUUCUCACAGAACUGUGACAUUUAUCCAGGGAAGGAUUUUGUACAACCACCUACCAAGAUUUGCGUGGGCUGCCCCAGAGAUAUACCCACCAACAGCCCAGAGCUGGAGGAGACACUGACUCACACCAUCACAAAGCUUAAUGCAGAGAAUAACGCAACUUUCUAUUUCAAGAUUGACAAUGUGAAAAAAGCAAGAGUACAGGUGGUGGCUGGCAAGAAAUAUUUUAUUGACUUCGUGGCCAGGGAAACCACAUGUUCCAAGGAAAGUAAUGAAGAGUUGACCGAAAGCUGUGAGACCAAAAAACUUGGCCAAAGCCUAGAUUGCAACGCUGAAGUUUAUGUGGUACCCUGGGAGAAAAAAAUUUACCCUACUGUCAACUGUCAACCACUGGGAAUGAUCUCACUGAUGAAAAGGCCUCCAGGUUUUUCACCUUUCCGAUCAUCACGAAUAGGGGAAAUAAAAGAAGAAACAACUGUAAGUCCACCCCACACUUCCAUGGCACCUGCACAAGAUGAAGAGCGGGAUUCAGGAAAAGAACAAGGGCAUACUCGUAGACAUGACUGGGGCCAUGAAAAACAAAGAAAACAUAAUCUUGGCCAUGGCCAUAAACAUGAACGUGACCAAGGGCAUGGGCACCAAAGAGGACAUGGCCUUGGCCAUGGACACGAACAACAGCAUGGUCUUGGUCAUGGACAUAAGUUCAAACUUGAUGAUGAUCUUGAACACCAAGGGGGCCAUGUCCUUGACCAUGGACAUAAGCAUAAGCAUGGUCAUGGCCACGGAAAACAUAAAAAUAAAGGCAAAAAGAAUGGAAAGCACAAUGGUUGGAAAACAGAGCAUUUGGCAAGCUCUUCUGAAGACAGUACUACACCUUCUGCACAGACACAAGAGAAGACAGAAGGGCCAACACCCAUCCCUUCCCUAGCCAAGCCAGGUGUAACAGUUACCUUUUCUGACUUUCAGGACUCUGAUCUCAUUGCAACUAUGAUGCCUCCUAUAUCACCAGCUCCCAUACAGAGUGAUGACGAUUGGAUCCCUGAUAUCCAGAUAGACCCAAAUGGCCUUUCAUUUAACCCAAUAUCAGAUUUUCCAGACACGACCUCCCCAAAAUGUCCUGGACGCCCCUGGAAGUCAGUUAGUGAAAUUAAUCCAACCACACAAAUGAAAGAAUCUUAUUAUUUCGAUCUCACUGAUGGCCUUUCUUAAUUUAAGUGGCUAUGGGUAUUUCUUUCAUACUUUAUUAAAGUAUCAAUAUCCCUCUCUCCAUUGUCCAGAUGAAAAUAUCCUGAUAUAAUGCACCAAAAACCAUGCAGCUUCGGAACAGUCUAAAGAGAAGUGGUGAGACUCCCAGUGGAGACACCAUCAGUCUCCACGGACUGCAUAAAAUUGUGUGCCACAAUUCUAACUCUUUUCUGAAUCUUCUUCCCAAGUUUUCUAAACUAGCACAGUAAACAGACAAACUAAUGUGCCGUAUGGCCUGCUGCAAUUGGCUUCUCUGAUAACAAAUAUGUACCUUACAACAUAUGUCAUGAAUUUGCAUACAAAGAUUCUUGUCAUUCUUAAUAAACUGUGGCACUUGGUAUUUGAAUGUGUGUGAAAAUAAGGGAAGUCAAGAGAUUAAAUGCUGAACUUAUUAAUGGAAUAGAAAUAAUAAGGAGGCUGAGGCUGGAGAAUUGCUUGAACCCGGGAGGCGGAGGUUGCAGUGAGCCGAGAUCGUGCCACUGCGCUCCAGCCUGGGCAUCAGAGCAAGAUUCUGUCUCAGAAAAAAAGAAAAAAAAAGAAAUAAUAAGAAAAACUUCCAGAUUUCAAAGUAACAAGAAAGAAGACAGGUUGGCCAAAGGGAGGAAAGGGGGGACAUAAAUUAAUUGACUUUCUAUUCCCAAAAUGGGCUAGUUAUAUCAAAUAAAUACUCCCACUGCCCUUUCUGAGUGAGAGUGUUUCUCAUAAGUCAAAAAUUUCUGUUUACUCAUUAACUACUCUUUGCAACAGGCUUUCAUAUAGAAGUAUUCUGUUUAUUUUUGCUGAGCCUAGAUUGAGUAAUUCUUAGUUUACAGAAGCUCCGAGCUUAAUGAUAAGGAUGAAAAGCAGAGGGAGCAAUAUAGAAGCAGGCUUGCUAAUAAAACUUUUUAAAUAAUUGACAAGGGAAUAUUAUGGAAUGUGAUGCAAAGUUUGUUCCGAAAUUUUAUGAGGAAAUUACUCUCUAGUCUCACUUUAUAGUCUUUUUGCUAUGACUUUGAAGACCAUUGAUUUUUGAGAAGCAGAAUAAUAGGAUUGCCUUUCAUUGCCCUAUAGUGCAAAGAAGGUAUAUGCUUUAUAACCAAUGUUGUACUUUUGCCUAGAAAAACAAGAUAUGGCUUUAAAUAGCUACAAUCAUCUUUGGAUGUAUAUGUCACUGCUGCUUCAAGUUAUUGGAUGCAUUUGAACCUCUGAGUUUGUCUUUCAUUUUAAAUAUUGUCUGUUCUUUUAAAUAAACAACCACAGAUGUCAGGAAAAAGUCUUACCUUGUCAACUGGUUGCUCCACUUUUUAAAAAUGAUUGAAUGAUAACAUCAUAUUAACUGCGUUUUACUAUACUUACAGAGUCACCUAAGGUCCUGCGAGUACAAGGGUCGACCCCCAAAGGCAGGGGCAGAGCCAGCAUCUGAGAGGGAGGUCUCUUGACCAAUGGGCAGAAUCUUCACUCCAGGCACAUAGCCCCAACCACCUCUGCCAGCAACCUUGAGAGGAAGGACAAGAAGAAAGAUGGGAUAGAAUUUAAAUAGAGAAGAAUGCCAUUUUAUCACUCUGCCUCUGGGUGAAAUAAAGAUCAGUCUUGAUGUUCUAACUCUAAUUCACAGUGGUCUCCUUUCAGCCCUACCCAUUCUGCAGCAAAUUCCAGCUGGUCAGAGAGUCAGUGCUGUGGCUCUGCCAUGGAGGCUCAUAACCCAACACUGGAACAUUCCCUAGCCAAGGCAGAAGUCCUUAGGCGGGACUUCCUUACCACCACGGGUGCUAAAAGAAGAGUUAGUAGGUCAUGCUUCUACCAGUAAUCUAAGGACUCUCUCCUUCUCUUCUUCCUCUUUCUCCAGAUUUCCAAGCCUUAGCUAAGAGUAAUUUGGCUUGUUUAGUAUUGUUUUCUUAUGGUCCAGUUAAUUACCAAAAAUAUUUUUAAAAUCAUCUCUGUUAAUAGAAUGUCUACCAACUUCUCACUAUCAGAAAAUACUCAACCUCCAAACAAUUUGAAAUUAUCUUUCUGAUCCAGGUAAAGAAGCAAAUUGAAAAUCAAUAAAGUAAAAAGUGACGGAGA